CUGACAGCCGUGUGCCUCGUGCCAGCUUAACCUCGCUGUUGGUUGAGGAAAGAGGGCUCAAGGCGAAAGAUCCAGGAAUGGAGGGCAGAACACAGGGAAGAGGUGGGAGGCGGGAGGUAGGCUGGGUGGGGGAGGUGGGAGGCAGAUCUGGGGGAGGCUUGAAUGCCAGGUAACGUGUGGCCAGGAAGGAGAUGCCGUCAGAUCUGUGUUUUGGGAAAGUUCUGGUCUAGAUGCAGUGCAUGAGGUGAGUGAAGAGACACCAGAGGAUGGGGCAGGUGUGGGAAGCCCCCGUUUAUGGGGAGAGGCAGGAAAAGUGGAGCAAGCAUCCUCGUCUGAGCCCAGUGCCAGGCGGGAGGAGGCCUGAGAAAAGCCAUCUGGUUCUGGUGACAUUGAAGGCCACCGGUGGUCUCAGAGGAUGACUGAGUGGGAGCCCAGUGGUGGGUGGGUAGGGUGGGAGGAGGUGAGGAGGGAAGGAGAGGCUCAGUGAGGGAGGCAGUUCAGAAUCAAGACCAGGAUGGGGCUCUGGGGGCGCCGCAUGCCAAAUGGGAAGUGAGUGGGUGAACUAGGAUCUGGGUGAUAUCACGUACUUAGGAAUAGAAUAGCCCAGGUCAGAUCAGGCACAAAAGGAUUGUGUGGAAAGGCAGAAGGUUCCAGAUGACUCGUGACAAGCUUUGGGGCCCAGCUCACAGUUCUCAGCAGAGCCCCGUGAACUGCGUGAACGUGAAUGUGCGGAAGAGAGACCACACUCGGGUGAGGACUGGCCCUGCCUGAUACAUUUAUUUUUGUUUUGGAAUUAGGAACAGAGAAAUGAAAUGGGAAGAGAUUAUCGGUAGGAAAAACAGUGGAAGACAGGGCUUGAGAUCUUGGCCUUUGAGCGGUUCUGUAAUCUCACAAGUAAUGAUCUGGGAUGACCUGAAGAAGAAGACUGUUAUUGAAAUAGAAUUUUCUACAGAAGUCAAGGCAGUCAAGCUGCGGCGAGAUAGGGCUCCGCUGGAGGUAAGUAGGUGGUGGCGUGGAUGACGUGCGCCACAGUGGACCAGCCAGUGGGUCUCACCGUGGUGAGUUAUGUCCCAUUCCGACAUGUGCAGAGCUGAGGACAUGAGUUUUGAGCCUUGAAUUACCCUGGGCUUUUAGCCCCUGCUUUGCCAAAUGCUGCCUCUCAAUAAAGGUUUUCGGUUUGAAGAUGGAGUGUUUGAUGAUGUCUCUCUGAACCUCAGAGACGUCUCUUAGGCUGACCUUCACCCAGGCGAGAAGCACUCCCUCAGCAGAGCCAGCCCACGUGCACUCGCCGAGCUCCAGGCCUGGCGCUGGCUACCUGCCUCCAGAGCUUUUUCUUCAGGAACACUCCUUUUCUGUGUGAAUUGUGGUGGUUUUGGACUCCAUGAUUAAGGUGUUCACAUUCACACACAAUCCCCAUCAGUUGCACGUCUUCGAAACCUGCUAUAACCCCAAAGGCCUCUGUGUCCUUUGUCCCAAUAGUAACAACUCCCUCCUGGCCUUUCCGGGCACGCACACGGGCCAUGUGCAGCUUGUGGACCUGGCCAGCACGGAGAAGCCACCCGUGGACAUUCCUGCACACGAGGGUGUCCUGAGCUGCAUUGCACUCAACCUGCAGGGAACAAGAAUUGCAACUGCAUCCGAGAAAGGGACGCUUAUAAGAAUAUUUGAUACUUCAUCAGGGCAUUUAAUCCAGGAACUGCGAAGAGGAUCUCAAGCAGCCAAUAUUUACUGCAUCAACUUCAAUCAGGAUGCGUCCCUCAUCUGCGUAUCCAGCGACCACGGCACAGUGCAUAUUUUUGCAGCUGAAGAUCCAAAAAGGAAUAAACAGUCCAGUUUGGCCUCAGCCAGUUUCCUUCCAAAAUACUUCAGUUCCAAGUGGAGUUUCUCCAAGUUUCAGGUUCCCUCAGGCUCUCCGUGCAUUUGUGCCUUUGGAACAGAGCCAAACGCCGUCAUUGCAAUUUGUGCAGACGGCAGCUACUACAAAUUCCUGUUCAACCCCAAGGGGGAGUGCAUCCGAGAUGUCUACGCGCAGUUUCUAGAGAUGACCGAUGACAAGCUGUGACUCCAGCUGGGGGCGCCACAGCACCCACCACCUGCCGCCUUCAGACUCUCGGGGCUGGUGCCAGUGCCCCAGGGGCCUCCUGGGCCACGGGCUGGAGGGGCUGCCCAGGGACCUUGGUCUCGAAGCCAUACGUGGUUGUCUGCUUUCCUAAGGACUCCCAUUUCCAGUAUUAAAGAGAGAAUCAUCAUCAAGGCACCGUAGGUAACUCAGUGGCUGUGACCAGCUCGACUGGCGGCCACUGGCUGUUCCCAUGAGUUCAGCUGUGACGUUAGCUUCAGUGGCUCCGCCGCAUCCUCACACUGACGGGGGCUCCAUACGGACCUGGGGACUGGGCUGAGAGGGUGGACGAGUUCAGGUUUGUUUUUGCAGCAGAUUCCGUCGUUCUUACUGAGUCUGCAGCGGGGGAGUGAACAAGUGUGCAGAUGUAAGUUCUUACAUGAUAAGCAGAUUGAAUACAACACCAGCAGCUUGCCUUAGAAAAGGAGAAAGGAAUUCCUUUUCCCGCCCGAACAUGAAGAAAAAUGACCUGACCCUGUAGAGAGAACACAGUGUGAAUGUUUCCCCUCGUGUGAGCCCAGCCUGUGGUCUUCUCCGUACCCGCAACGUGGUCAUCUGUGCCCGUGACGUCACCUGUGCCCGUGCGUGGCGUCCCCGUCUCCGUUGGGGCCAUUAGAAUGAGGCAGACACCAGGCCACUCUAGAAGCCGAGCCGUCACACCUCAGGCGUGUGCGGGGCGGGGACGGGGGGUCUCCUGGUUACAUUUUGGAUUAAACCUGUUUCCCGGUUAUGUGUAGGGAACAGCAGAGUGAUGCACGAACUUUGAACAUUCGUUAUGGGGAAAACAUCCUUUAACUUCGGGGUCGUCUGCCAGAGCAGGGUCUGGGAGGGUCCAUGCAGUUCCCGCUGGUGUGGAGGGAAAUGCCCUGGUCUGGCCUCCGAGCCCCCAGGUCCACCGUCUCCCCUCCCCUCAUUUGUAAGAAUAGCUACACACUAACAUUUUGGGAAGGAGAGGCACAUAACUUUUUUUAACAUUUGGUAACUAGGUUAUGGGCUCUACAUUGUCAGCUACUUGGGAUAUAUAUUUAAUUUUCUUAAAUUCCCGUUAAACUCUAUUUUAUGGUUUUGAUUUCAGAUUGCAAACAUGUAAAACCUGCAUAGCAGCGAGUUCUCGGUUUUGCCGGUUUCUUUAGUUCUUUACUGUCACUGUCAUGUAAUCAGCUAAUUCUCUGUGGAUGUUGCUGUAAAGUAUGCAUGUUCCUUUCAUGUGUAUUUAAUCAUGAUGUUUAAUUUUGCACACUUAUUUGUAAUGUUUCUUUUAAAUAAAAGUGACUAAUUUUGUUGUAGUCUGGACCUGUAA